CUCUCCUCCCCCUUUCUCUCUAAGGAUGGCCCAGAAGGAGAACUCCUACCCCUGGCCCUACGGCCGACAGACGUACGGGUCCCAAGUUUGACGACAGAACCCGCUCUGGUCAUUUGUAGCCACAUCCUGUCAGGUGCUGCCAACGUGAAUCUGACCAGCCAGUGACUCCCAGCUGGCUCCAUCUGGCCUGAGCACCCUGCCCCAGCGAGUCCUCCGGAAAGAGCCUGUCACCCCAUCUGCACUUGUCCUCAUGAGCCGCUCCAAUGUCCAGCCCACAGCUGCCCCUGGCCAGAAGGUGAUGGAGAAUAGCAGUGGGACACCCGACAUCUUAACGCGGCACUUCACAAUUGAUGACUUUGAGAUUGGGCGUCCUCUGGGCAAAGGCAAGUUUGGAAACGUGUACUUGGCUCGGGAGAAGAAAAGCCAUUUCAUCGUGGCGCUCAAGGUCCUCUUCAAGUCCCAGAUAGAGAAGGAGGGCGUGGAGCAUCAGCUGCGCAGAGAGAUCGAAAUCCAGGCCCACCUGCACCAUCCCAACAUCCUGCGUCUCUACAACUAUUUUUAUGACCGGAGGAGGAUCUACUUGAUUCUAGAGUAUGCCCCCCGCGGGGAGCUCUACAAGGAGCUGCAGAAGAGCUGCACAUUUGACGAGCAGCGAACAGCCACGAUCAUGGAGGAGUUGGCAGAUGCUCUAAUGUACUGCCAUGGGAAGAAGGUGAUUCACAGAGACAUAAAGCCAGAAAAUCUGCUCUUAGGGCUCAAGGGAGAGCUGAAGAUUGCUGACUUCGGCUGGUCUGUGCAUGCGCCCUCCCUGAGGAGGAAGACAAUGUGUGGCACCCUGGACUACCUGCCCCCAGAGAUGAUUGAGGGGCGCAUGCACAAUGAGAAGGUGGAUCUGUGGUGCAUUGGAGUGCUUUGCUAUGAGCUGCUGGUGGGGAACCCACCCUUUGAGAGUGCAUCACACAACGAGACCUAUCGCCGCAUCGUCAAGGUGGACCUAAAGUUCCCCGCUUCCGUGCCCAUGGGAGCCCAGGACCUCAUCUCCAAACUGCUCAGGCAUAACCCCUCGGAACGGCUGCCCCUGGCCCAGGUCUCAGCCCACCCUUGGGUCCGGGCCAACUCUCGGAGGGUGCUGCCUCCCUCUGCCCUUCAAUCUGUCGCCUGAUGGUCCCUGUCAUUCACUCGGGUGCGUGUGUUUGUAUGUCUGUGUAUGUAUAGGGGAAAGAAGGGAUCCCUAACUGUUCCCUUAUCUGUUUUCUACCUCCUCCUUUGUUUAAUAAAGGCUGAAGCUUUUUGUACUCAUGA